AGUAUCUUACCAGAUGUACUUUGAAGCAUCAGCAACUAAAAAUGAUAGGAGCUGAAAUUUACUGGAAUCAUUUUAAGAAGAGAAGAAACAGUGACUCAUCCUCCUGGAAAGAAAUUUCAAGGGAUAAAGCACCAUGGAUCUAACUUAUAUUCCCGAAGACCUAUCCAGUUGUCCAAAAUUUGUAAAUAAAUCCUGUCCUCCCACCAACCGCUCUUUUCAUGUCCAGCAUGCUCGAGUCAUCAGCCAUGUGCCUGAAAACACAAAGGGGGCAGUGAAAAAACACCUAUCCAAGAAAAAGGACAGGAAAGCAGCGAAGACACUGGUGGAGAAGGUGGCCAGUUCUCAGACAGAGGAAGAGUAGAAAUCAUAAAUGAGAGCUGUCUUCAUCCAAGGUGCUGAAGAGCACCCUGCGGCAUUCUGCUACCAGGUGAAUGGGUCUUGCCCCAGGACAGUACAUACUCUGGGCAUCCAGUUGGUCAUCUACCUGGCCUGUGCAGCAGGCAUGCUGAUUAUCGUGCUAGGGAAUGUAUUUGUGGCAUUUGCUGUGUCCUACUUCAAAGCGCUUCACACGCCCACCAACUUCCUGCUGCUCUCCCUGGCCCUGGCUGACAUGUUUCUGGGUCUGCUGGUGCUGCCCCUCAGCACCAUUCGCUCAGUGGAGAGCUGCUGGUUCUUCGGGGACUUCCUCUGCCGCCUGCACACCUACCUGGACACCCUCUUCUGCCUCACCUCCAUCUUCCAUCUCUGUUUCAUUUCCAUUGACCGCCACUGUGCCAUCUGUGACCCCCUGCUCUAUCCCUCCAAGUUCACAGUGAGGGUGGCUCUCAGGUACAUCCUGGCAGGAUGGGGGGUGCCCGCAGCAUACACUUCGUUAUUCCUCUACACAGAUGUGGUAGAGACAAGGCUCAGCCAGUGGCUGGAAGAGAUGCCUUGUGUGGGCAGUUGCCAGCUGCUGCUCAAUAAAUUUUGGGGCUGGUUAAACUUCCCUUUGUUCUUUGUCCCCUGCCUCAUUAUGAUCAGCUUGUAUGUGAAGAUCUUUGUGGUUGCUACCAGACAGGCUCAGCAGAUUACCACAUUGAGCAAAAGCCUGGCUGGGGCUGCCAAGCAUGAGAGAAAAGCUGCCAAGACCCUGGGCAUUGCUGUGGGCAUAUACCUCUUGUGCUGGCUGCCCUUCACCAUAGACACGAUGGUCGACAGCCUCCUUCACUUUAUCACACCCCCACUGGUCUUUGACAUCUUUAUCUGGUUUGCUUACUUCAACUCAGCCUGCAACCCCAUCAUCUAUGUCUUUUCCUACCAGUGGUUUCGGAAGGCACUGAAACUCACACUGAGCCAGAAGGUCUUCUCACCGCAGACACGCACUGUUGAUUUGUACCAAGAAUGAUUCCUUCUACUAAAUGCAGGCAAGGAGUAGGACCUCACAGGAAAGAUAAGUGGCACUGUGACCGUGGGCUGUGUGGUGUUG